AGGCGCCGAGGUGCGCGCGGAGCGAGGUGGCCGCAGCGUCUCCGCGCGCGGCCCAAGCCCGGCAGGAGUGCGGAACCGCCGCCUCGGCCAUGCGGCUCCCGGCCGGGGGGCCUGGGCUGGGGCCCGCGCCGCCCCCCGCGCUCCGCCCCCGCUGAGCCUGAGCCCGACCCGGGGCGCCUCCCGCCAGGCACCAUGGUGCAGAAGUCGCGCAACGGCGGCGUAUACCCCGGCCCGAGCGGGGAGAAGAAGCUGAAGGUGGGCUUCGUGGGGCUGGACCCCGGCGCGCCCGACUCCACCCGGGACGGGGCGCUGCUGAUCGCCGGCUCCGAGGCCCCCAAGCGCGGCAGCAUCCUCAGCAAACCUCGCGCGGGCGGCGCGGGCGCCGGGAAGCCCCCCAAGCGCAACGCCUUCUACCGCAAGCUGCAGAAUUUCCUCUACAACGUGCUGGAGCGGCCGCGCGGCUGGGCGUUCAUCUACCACGCCUACGUGUUCCUCCUGGUUUUCUCCUGCCUCGUGCUGUCUGUGUUUUCCACCAUCAAGGAGUAUGAGAAGAGCUCGGAGGGGGCCCUCUACAUCCUGGAAAUCGUGACUAUCGUGGUGUUUGGCGUGGAGUACUUCGUGCGGAUCUGGGCCGCAGGCUGCUGCUGCCGGUACCGUGGCUGGAGGGGGCGGCUCAAGUUUGCCCGGAAACCGUUCUGUGUGAUUGACAUCAUGGUGCUCAUCGCCUCCAUUGCGGUGCUGGCCGCCGGCUCCCAGGGCAACGUCUUUGCCACAUCUGCGCUCCGGAGCCUGCGCUUCCUGCAGAUUCUGCGGAUGAUCCGCAUGGACCGGCGGGGAGGCACCUGGAAGCUGCUGGGCUCUGUGGUCUAUGCCCACAGCAAGGAGCUGGUCACUGCCUGGUACAUCGGCUUCCUUUGUCUCAUCCUGGCCUCGUUCCUGGUGUACUUGGCAGAGAAGGGGGAGAACGACCACUUUGACACCUACGCGGAUGCACUCUGGUGGGGCCUGAUCACGCUGACCACCAUUGGCUACGGGGACAAGUACCCCCAGACCUGGAACGGCAGGCUCCUUGCGGCAACCUUCACCCUCAUCGGUGUCUCCUUCUUCGCGCUGCCUGCAGGCAUCUUGGGGUCUGGGUUUGCCCUGAAGGUUCAGGAGCAGCACAGGCAGAAGCACUUUGAGAAGAGGCGGAACCCGGCAGCAGGCCUGAUCCAGUCGGCCUGGAGAUUCUACGCCACCAACCUCUCGCGCACAGACCUGCACUCCACGUGGCAGUACUACGAGCGAACGGUCACCGUGCCCAUGUACAGUUCGCAAACUCAAACCUACGGGGCCUCCAGACUUAUCCCCCCGCUGAACCAGCUGGAGCUGCUGAGGAACCUCAAGAGUAAAUCUGGACUCGCUUUCAGGAAGGACCCCCCGCCGGAGCCGUCUCCAAGCCAGAAGGUCAGUUUGAAAGAUCGUGUCUUCUCCAGCCCCCGAGGCGUGGCUGCCAAGGGGAAGGGGUCCCCGCAGGCCCAGACUGUGAGGCGGUCACCCAGCGCCGACCAGAGCCUCGAGGACAGCCCCAGCAAGGUGCCCAAGAGCUGGAGCUUCGGGGACCGCAGCCGGGCACGCCAGGCUUUCCGCAUCAAGGGUGCCGCGUCACGGCAGAACUCAGAAGAAGCAAGCCUCCCCGGAGAGGACAUUGUGGAUGACAAGAGCUGCCCCUGCGAGUUUGUGACCGAGGACCUGACCCCGGGCCUCAAAGUCAGCAUCAGAGCCGUGUGUGUCAUGCGGUUCCUGGUGUCCAAGCGGAAGUUCAAGGAGAGCCUGCGGCCCUACGACGUGAUGGACGUCAUCGAGCAGUACUCAGCCGGCCACCUGGACAUGCUGUCCCGAAUUAAGAGCCUGCAGUCCAGGAUAGAUAUGAUUGUGGGUCCCCCGCCCCCUUCAACUCCCCGGCACAAGAAGUACCCCACCAAAGGACCCACGGCCCCUCCGAGAGAGUCACCCCAGUACUCACCUAGAGUGGACCAGAUCGUGGGGCGGGGCCCAGCGAUCACGGACAAGGACCGCACCAAGGGCCCGGCCGAGGCGGAGCUGCCCGAGGACCCCAGCAUGAUGGGACGGCUCGGGAAGGUGGAGAAGCAGGUCUUGUCCAUGGAGAAGAAGCUGGACUUCCUGGUGAAUAUCUACAUGCAGCGGAUGGGCAUCCCCCCGACAGAGACCGAGGCCUACUUUGGGGCCAAAGAGCCGGAGCCGGCGCCGCCGUACCACAGCCCGGAAGACAGCCGGGAGCAUGUCGACAGGCACGGCUGCAUUGUCAAGAUCGUGCGCUCCAGCAGCUCCACGGGCCAGAAGAACUUCUCGGCGCCCCCGGCCGCGCCCCCUGUCCAGUGUCCGCCCUCCACCUCCUGGCAGCCACAGAGCCACCCGCGCCAGGGCCACGGCACCUCCCCCGUGGGGGACCACGGCUCCCUGGUGCGCAUCCCGCCGCCGCCUGCCCACGAGCGGUCGCUGUCCGCCUACGGCGGGGGCAACCGCGCCAGCAUGGAGUUCCUGCGGCAGGAGGACACCCCGGGCUGCAGGCCCCCCGAGGGGAACCUGCGGGACAGCGACACGUCCAUCUCCAUCCCGUCCGUGGACCACGAGGAGCUGGAGCGUUCCUUCAGCGGCUUCAGCAUCUCCCAGUCCAAGGAGAACCUGGAUGCUCUCAACAGCUGCUACGCGGCCGUGGCGCCUUGUGCCAAAGUCAGGCCCUACAUUGCGGAGGGAGAGUCAGACACCGACUCCGACCUCUGUACCCCGUGCGGGCCCCCGCCACGCUCGGCCACCGGCGAGGGUCCCUUUGGUGACGUGGGCUGGGCCGGGCCCAGGAAGUGAGGCGGCGCUGGGCCAGUGGACCCGCCCGCGGCCCUCCUCAGCACGGUGCCUCCGAGGUUUUGAGGCGGGAACCCUCUGGGGCCCUUUUCUUACAGUAACUGAGUGUGGCGGGAAGGGUGGGCCCUGGAGGGGCCCAUGUGGGCUGAAGGAUGGGGGCUCCUGGCAGUGACCUUUUACAAAAGUUAUUUUCCAACAGGGGCUGGAGGGCUGGGCAGGGCCCUGUGGCUCCAGGAGCAGCGUGCAGGAGCAAGGCUGCCCUGUCCACUCUGCUCAGGGCCGCGGCCGACAUCAGCCCGGUGUGAGGAGGGGCGGGAGUGAUGACGGGGUGUUGCCAGCGUGGCAACAGGCGGGGGGUUGUCUCAGCCGAGCCCAGGGGAGGCACAAAGGGCAGGCCUGUUCCCUGAGGACCUGCGCAAAGGGCGGGCCUGUUUGGUGAGGACCUGCGGCCUUGGGUCCCGGUGGGGUUUCCGGGCAGCUACAGGCGGGUGUGGCCGGCCGCUGUGCGUGGCCUCUGCCUUCACACCUGACCUGCCCGGCGGGCUUUCCUGUUCCCCACCUCAGGGGCGCCCAAAUACAGAGCUAUUGGUUGGCGUCUUCUCCCUGUACCUUCUGGGAUCUGAGGGCUCUUUCCAUGGAAGCCAGCCCCGAGGUGGAGACCUUCGCCUGCAGCCGAGGAGCGGGUGGGGCCUGGGAACCAAACUGGAGCCAGAGUGGACGUCCAGCCCUCUGGUCUUGGCCUCCAGAGGGAGGGCCUGGCUCACGGUGGGGCCAGGGAGCCGGCUCCAAAGGGUCUUCAAAAAGGGGGUCCUUGGGGGCUCCAGCUGCCUCGCCCUGGCCUUUCUGUGGGUGCGUGAGAGCCAGCAGCACCCCAGCCUUGGAGACCGGGGGGGCAGGACCCCAAGUCCUCCCCUCUCUCCUGACUGCCCUGGCCGGGUGCCGGCACUGCGAGACCCACCUGGUGAGCAGGCCUCACAGUUCUUAGCCAGGGCCCCACCUCGCCUGUGUCCCACCAGUGCCCCGACAGACCUGGGGCAGGGCUGGGCCAUGAUGCAGCGGGCCAGGAUAGCCUCCACCGUCAGCACAGGGCCGCCCUCCCCGCCUUUCCGGAGGAAACCACUCCCACCUCAGCCCAGCUGUGCGCCCUCCCUAGCUCUCCUGCCCCCUGGAGCUGAUGGCCCCUUCUCCACUGACCGAUUCCUUAGCGGGGCCUCUUGGGGUCUCGGGCCUCGGGUGCACCGUCCCAUGCCCGUCCUGUUGUGGGCACCGUGGCCCUUGGGGCAGGCGGCUCUAAUGCGGGAGCGAGUCCCUAGCUCCAGACUUAAGAACCAGACCCCGGGAGCAUCUGGCAUUUGGCGUGACGGCGUCGCAGGCGGGCCUGGGCUCCCUGGAGAGUGGCCUCCCUGGGAGUGAGCAGGGCUGGGGUCGUGGGCGCAAAUACUCCUGCAGAGCAAGUGCAGGGGAGUCCUGGGCCCGUUUCUCCUCCACCUGCGUUUUCAGUGCACUUGGCUUGGCUGGGAGGUCCUGAGGCCCUGAGGCCAGCAGGGGAACCAGUCCUGAGGGAGAGGACUUUGAAAGCAGCAUUUGAGGGUCGUACGCCCCUGGCUGGUGGGGGUCCUGGCGCUCAGGGUGUUCGGGGAGCCAUGUCUGGCGUCCAUUGUGGGGAGCUGCUGCCCUGGCCUCUCUGCCUACCCCCAGCCCGGCCAGGGCACUCCCAGGCCCUGUCGCCAUUGAGGUGCCUCCGCUGGGCUGUCUCCUCACCCCUCCCUGUGCUGGAGCCUGUCCCAAAAAGGUGCCAACUGGGAGGCCUCGGAAGCCACUGUCCAGGCUCCCACUGCCUGUCUGCUCUGUUCCCAAAGGCAGCGUGUGUGGCCUCGGGCCCUGCGGUGGCAUGAAGCAUCCCUUCUGGUGUGGGCAUCGCUACGUGUUUUGGGGGCAGCGUUUCACGGCGGUGCCCUUGCUGUCUCCCUUGGGCUGGCUCGAGCCUGGGGUCCAUGUCCCUUUGCCGUCCCGUCAUGGGGCAGGGAAUCCAUAGCGGGGCCCACAGGCAGGGGUAUGAGUGCGUCCCACCCAACGCAGCACCAGCCCCGGCCACCGCUCCCCGUGUCCCCAGUUCCGUCUCAGCUACCUGGACUCCAGGACCCUGGAGAAGGGAGACCUGGCAGUGGAGGGAGGCUGUGCUGUGUGUCCCCCUGCAGGUGUGACCCCGCCUGCUCUUUCCUCCCCCGCCAGGUGUGGCCCCGCCUGCUCUUUCCUCCCCCACCAGUAUGGCCCCACCUGCUCUUUCCUCCCCCCCCAAGGUGUGGCCCCACCUGUUCUUUCCUCCCCUGCCGAGGUGUGACCCCACCUGCUCUUUCCUCCCUCCCAGUAUGGCCCCACCUGCUCUUUCCUCCCCCGAGGUGAGGCCCCGCCUGCUCUUUCCUCCCAUGGGGCCGCUGAGGCAUGAGCACCUGGGCACAGGUUGGGGCUCUGCAGGAUGAGGAAGACAGGCCAAUCCCUUCCCUCCCAGAAGCUGGCCGCCCAGCAGGAGGGACUGAGGCCAGACUCAUGUCCAGCAAGGAACGUGUGGUGUGUCCCCUGGGAAGUCUCUGGGCCCUGGGAAGAGGGAAGGUGCACGUCCUGGGAUGGUUGCGGGGCCCUGUUUUGGGAGACAAAGGGGUAGAGGGUCUGUCUUGGGCCCCCCCAGACUCUAGCCUGAGCAGUGCAGCCACCUACUGCCCCACCUCAGAGAAGUGCAGCGGGAAGGAGGCUGGAGGUGGUGCGGCGCUGCCUCGGGUGUCUGCGUGAAUGAGCGUGGCCAAGGACCAGUGCCACCUCAUGGCAAAGAGCUCCCGCAGUGUUUGUUAGAGUGCACAUCCCUACGUGCCCACUGGCACACACACGUGCUCACAUACAUGUCCGCAUACAGGCGUACACAUGCACGCUUGCACACAUGCACACAGACCACAUAGCACACAUGUGCACUGACCACACCUGUAUAGACCAUGCACAGUACACAUACGUGCAUACACAUGCCUGCAUACAGGCAUACACAUGCACGCUUACAUGUACACGUGCACAGAUCACACACAUGCACACACGUGUAGCUCACACACAGUAUACACAUACACAAGUGCACAGACCACACACAGCACUAACACAUGCACACACAAAGUGCAUAGGCCACACAGCACAUGCACACAGGUGCACAGACCACACAGCACACACAAGUGCACAGAGCACACUGCACACAUGCACACACACACGCGUGCAUGCACACUCCUCGCACUUCCAGCCUUGGAGCCCUUCUGUCUCUGGUCUUUCUCUUUGACCCUGCUGAGUGUAAGCUGCCUGGGGAGGGGCUACAAGGAGUAAUUGUGGCUUUAGGGGUCGUGGUGAUGCUGGAAUGUCAAGCGCCGUCGUGGGGUAUCCGACUGUCCGGGCUCCUGGUCCGCAGUGGCAGAGCGCCAGGCAGAGCCCAAUCAGGGUCUCGUGCUGCCCUUCCCUCCCACAGCCUGGCAGCCAUCCAGAGGAGGGGCUCUACCAGAUGCCAAGGUGCCCCGGUGUCUGUAUGGGUGUCCGGUUGGGUCCUGUGUUUGGUCUGCCCUGGAGGUGCUGGGCCCUCCUGGGAUGGGUGGCUCAGCCUCGAAUCCCAGGCCCCAGCCCAGGCAGGUGCUGCUGCCUGUUGUGGUUUCCUGGCCCAGCUUCUCCUUCUCCCUCUGCAUAAAAUCACAGUCCGUGAGUCUUCCAGCUGCCACCACGGCUGGGACACGCUGGGGGAGGGCUCCUCCCAUGCCUCCUGCACACAGCCGUCUGAGCAGGGCAGGUGCCCAACACCCCCCACCGGAGGACACGCUGCCCCUCAGCGAUGCCCCUACCUUUUGGGGGGCCUCGUCUCAAGCCCCCCCUUGGAGGCUGAAAUCACCCCAGGCACUGUGAGGGCUUCUCCAGGGGGCACCCUUUGAGCUGUGGGUCUGAUCACCCCAAGUCCCGCCCGGAGGAGAGGCACAGCCAGGGCGUGUGGUUUAAUGUUUGCCCCCUUCGGGGCUGGAGGUCUCAGUGUUUCUAGAUUCCAGACCCUGCUGCCAGAGAGACCUGCUGCCGGAGAGAAGGGGAGGAGGACUCCAGCUGGGCUCGGUCCCCCACAGUCAGGGACCCCCAUAAAGGACACCCCCUUCUCUCUAGAAAGAGCUGGGCUCUCAGCUAUUUCUAGUUGCUUCCCAGAAGCCGAGGAGCAGAAGGAGCUGUGAGAGCUUUGCAGAAACGCCCUUGUCCCCGCCCUCCUGAGCUAUGAAUGCCGUACAGAGCAGAGGCUGGGGCAUUGGCAAGAUCACAGGUUGAUGCUGCACAGCCCCAUUGACACAAACCCUCAAAGCAGACGUGAGAGGGACGGUUCACAAAGCUCGGACCUGCCGUGGAGGGUGCCCGGCAGACGUGGCGUGAGAGGGACGGCUCACGAGGCUUGGACCUGCUGUGGAGGGUGCCCAGCAGACGUGGUGUGAGAGGAACGGCUCACGAGACUUGGACCUGGUGGAGGGUGCCCAGCAGACGUGGUGUGAGAGGGACGGCUCACAGGGCUUGGACCUGCCAUGGAGGGUGCCCGGCAGACGUGGUGUGAGAGGGAUGGUUCACAGGGCUUGGACCUGCCAUGGAGGGUGCCCGGCAGAUGUGGUGGGAGAGAGAUGGCUCAUGAGGCUUGGACCUGCCGUGGAGGGUGCCCAGCAGACGUGGUAUGAGAGGGAUGGCUCACGAGGCUUGGACCUGGUGGAGGGUGCCCGGCAGACGUGUGAGAGGGACGGUUCACAAGGCUUGGACCUGCCAUGGAGGGUGCCCAGCAGACGUGGUGUGAGAGGGACAGCUCACGAGGCUUGGACCUGCUGUGGAGGGUGCCCAGCAGGGGGCUGAGCUCUGAGGGGUGGGUGCUCAGUGCACGGGUGCCCCCAGUGUCCUCUGAUCCUGUCCGGUGCCUCCCCCAACCCCCACACCCAUGCAGAACUCCCAGGUCACAUGCACGUAUGUCCAGGGCAUGGGGGUGGCGUGAAGAGGCCUGGUCAGGGCCUUUAGGGGCUGCAGGACGGAAUGGCCGCCUGGGGAGCCUGUGUGGCUGUGCCGGGCAGCCAUCCUGCAUUCCCACCCAGCGCGCAGUCUCCACCUCGGCCCCAGCAAAGCGCUAAGCAGCCGGAGAGACAGCCAGGGCGGCUUCCUGAAGGAUGUGGGAUGGUGGACUCCGGGGUCGAGGGAAUACGCAGGUUCCUGUCCCUCCGGGAGACCUAGAGAAGCUGCACACCCAGGAGCUUUCCAUGACCCGGGAGCAUGAGUGAAUGGGGGUUCCAGUUUGCUGAACUUUGCCGUCUUGUAAGGGUGGGGGCUGACGGCCGACCCUGGGAGGAGGUGACAUCGCCGGGGGAGGUUGUGGGCAACGGUGGAGGAGGAGAGACGGGAGGGGACCAUUUGGGAUGGAGGGGCCUCUUCAGAGUUUUAAAAGGCGUUUGUGGGGUGGAGUUGAGUGUGCUCUGGGCUUGGACACUUGCCGUGGUGCCCCUGGCUGGCCGAGGAGACUGGCUCUGGCCAGGGGCCCCGUCCUGAGAGGUCCUCAGCGUCUGACUCUCGGCCAGGCGCCAGCAAGGAGGGGCCGGUCCCCGGGGCUACCAGGCAGGCACGUGCACAUCGCCAUCGCCACACGCCAACUCCGCCUGGGUUUUACAAAGUCGUUGCCUUAAUGCAUGUGGACAGGAACUCCCUGAGGUCGCCCCAUGCCCCCUGGCUGUGCCAGGUACGGACGCCCUGGACCCUGCGAACAGGUGGGGCGGGCGAGGGGCCCAAGGGACGGGCUCCAGAGACACGCGCAGGGCAGGAGGGGUCUCACGGAGGGGUCUCGCACUGAGGCGCCCAGAGCUGGUGGUCCCGCUGGACGCCAUCCCUCUGCCCGGGAUCCACACGGCCCACGUGUGCCCGCCAUGCCCGCGCCCCACGCCAUUGCAGUCUGCCAUCCUCUGGCCGUGACGGUGGCUGCAGCUUCCCCAUUUGCGCCGUUGCCUCUGGCUGUCUGCACUUUUGUUCAUGCUCCAAAGAACAUUUCAUAAUGCCUUCAGUACCGACGUACACUUCUGACCAUUUUGUAUGUGUCCUUGUGCCGUAGUGACCAGGCCUUUUUUUGGUGGAUGUGUUACCCCGCACACUUCAAUCUCAACUUUGUGCACCGUCCAUUUUCUAGGGAUAGACGCCCAGGGAAUGAACUCUAGUUUUCUAACAGAUUAGCUGAGAUAUUAACUUACUCACACGGACAGGUUGAUGCCAGAGCCGUAAGAAUGCGCCAGUGCGGGUUUGCGGGGGACUUCGGGUGUGGGGUCCUGCGGCCGCGAUGGCCGUGGAAGGUUCUGGGGAUCCCUGCUGCCACGGGGACGAGUUCGGACGCCAGGUGGACCUGUGCACUCAGUAAAACGCAGUGAUUCAACCUGGA